AGUCCCCGCUCUGCUCUGUCCGGUCACAGGACUUUUUGCCCUCUGUUCCCGGGUCCCUCAGGCGGCCACCCAGUGGGCACACUCCCAGGCGGCGCUCCGGCCCCGCGCUCCCUCCCUCUGCCUUUCAUUCCCAGCUGUCAACAUCCUGGAAGCUUUGAAGCUCAGGAAAGAAGAGAAAUCCACUGAGAACAGUCUGUAAAGCAUUGUGGGUUGGCAAUGGCUGUAUCCCUCUAAGGAAGGCCACAGUUCCGGUUGGGGGCCUCUCUUCAGCGGCUACAGCUUUUUCUACUGUCUGGUCCGUAGUGCUAUCUACAUCCAGACGGUGGAAGGGAGAGAAAGAGAAAGAAGGUAUCCUAGGAAUACCUGCCUGCUUAGACCCUCUAUAAAAGCUCUGUGCAUCCUGCCACUGAGGACUCCGAAGAGGUAGCAGUCUUCUGAAAGACUUCAACUGUGAGGACAUGUCGUUCAGAUUUGGCCAACAUCUCAUCAAGCCCUCUGUAGUGUUUCUCAAAACAGAACUGUCCUUCGCUCUUGUGAAUAGGAAACCUGUGGUACCAGGACAUGUCCUUGUGUGCCCGCUGCGGCCAGUGGAGCGCUUCCAUGACCUGCGUCCUGAUGAAGUGGCCGAUUUGUUUCAGACGACCCAGAGAGUCGGGACAGUGGUGGAAAAACAUUUCCAUGGGACCUCUCUCACCUUUUCCAUGCAGGAUGGCCCCGAAGCCGGACAGACUGUGAAGCACGUUCACGUCCAUGUUCUUCCCAGGAAGGCUGGAGACUUUCACAGGAAUGACAGCAUCUAUGAGGAGCUCCAGAAACAUGACAAGGAGGACUUUCCUGCCUCUUGGAGAUCAGAGGAGGAAAUGGCAGCAGAAGCCGCAGCUCUGCGGGUCUACUUUCAGUGACACAGGUAAAGACUGCAUUUCGUCAUUACCCAGACCCUCCCGUGGGCCUCAGGAAAGAGGCUGCACUCUCAGAAUGGGGAUGCACAAAAACACCUUCACCAGCAUCCUUGGGUGGUGGCUGCAAAGGACAAAGAGCUGGAGGGGAGAAAACCCUGGCCCUUGAGUACUGUAUUCCCAGCCUCCCAGUCUCUUCCAACUCUCCUGCCUCUUCACUCUCUUCUUCCAAGCCAGUGCCCCCAGCCCACCACCACCUUUCUCCAGUCUUUCCUGCGGUGGUGCUCCUCCAGAAUCCAAUGUUCACAAAGCAGACCUUCUGUCAUGCACAACUUCUUGUUUAAAAGGUCAACCCCAACUUAACUUAAAGGUGUGACAUGGCCCUUAGGCUCAAGUCUGUCUGCAAAGCCCUGUAAACCAGCUUUCUCUGCCUCCCUAACACGCCCCCGGGCAAACUCCUCUGCUUUCACUGAGUGGACUCUUCUCUUCAGUUGCUAUUUGGUAAAUUGCCCUUCAUGUUUCCCUUUAUGUUCGGCUCCUAGGAAGCUCAGGCCACAGGGAAAAGUCAAGGCUUGAUAGAAUUAAUCUUUGUCUUAAUGAUGACUAACUGUUGAGAGAUCAUAGGUUUAAGACUCUGGUAGAAAGAUAGCUAUAGCCAAUUUCCUUGUCAAAAUGCUUCUACUCCAAAUUUUUAUGCAGUGUCUAACGAGCUCAUGCCUAGAUCUAUCUGGCAAUCUAUAUUAUCCCUCCUAGUCUCAGUUCACAUAGUAGACUGCUGGAAUGACUGAGGGUGAUGUUUGGCCUGUAAACAAAAAGUGUUAAAGAAGGCCAGGUACAGUGGCUCAUGCCUAUAAUCCCAACUACUUGGGAAGCUGAGGCAGGAGAACUGCUUGAACCUGGGAGGCAGAGGUUGCAGUGAGCUGAGAUCAUGCCACUGCAUUCCAGCCUGGGUGACAGAGCAAGACUCAGUUUCAAAAAAACAGGAGAGAGAGAGAGAGAAAUGUAUCUAUCUCUCUGAAAUUUGUUUAUAAAUAUAGGGUUACCAUGCAAUACUGGCAUAUAUCUAGACUAAAAAAAUUACUUGUUUAUCUGAAAUUCAAAUUUAACUGGUAUCUUGUAUUUUUUUCUGGCAAACCUGUUAAUAAACUCCCAUGGACCCCAGUUACAGAUCCUCUCCUAUAAAUAGUUUCUUUUUUGUUUUUAGAAUUAGAUAAUUCCAAAUUAAAAUUAGGCAAUUCUUCAUCUGACCUGUGAAUAAAUAUGUUCAUGUUAUAAGUUGCAGAAGUAGAUCAGACACAAAUAAAAAACAAAAUUAGUGAAUAAAUGCUGUUAGCAAUUGAUUGGAAAAAAUUGUAUCAACCACUUAGUGAUCAUGAUUUUUAGCUAGAAAACACAUUCAUUGUAUUCUGAUUUCACCUUGAAAUGUAAGUAAGUCUUUACUGGAUAGCUUUAAAUAUAUGUGCACUUGGCCUUUCUCUCCCCAGCCCUCUUUUUAGAGUAUUCUAAAUAGUUAAAGACCCAGACUACCUUGCCCCCUAUUGUUGUUCAAAUAUGGUGUUGUACUCAGAUCCUUGCAUUCUAGAAAGCUUAUUUCAUUCUCCCAUGUCAUAAGUUUGUCAGCUCUGCACUCAGUUGCCUGGGGGGAUAUGGCAAGUGCUAUAACAGAGGCUGUCUUUCAUAUUUUAUUUUGAACCUUUUCCACUGUUCACCAUCUCUCUCUCGUUUUUUAAGGAUCAAGCUAGUUUAGUUUACCUAAGAACAUAGGCCUAUGGGCAUGACUACAAACCUCUUUCUGUUCCUCUUAUGAAGGCCAGUAUGUCAUUUUAGAGUGCCCUGUUCAAAUUUAAAUGGGGUGACAAUACCUCAGACUUGACUGCCUAGGUUGAAUUUUUUCUCCUGGGUUUUCUAUGCAGUGGGUAUUUUCAGGUAGAGGCUAGAAAGCUUUAGCCUUUUUCCCAAGGCUUGCUGAAUUGUAGGAGUUUUGUCUUAGAAUGCUUUUUCUAGACACUUUAAGAACUUUAAGAAGAUUCAAACUUAUUACCCAAAUUUCCUGUAGGCUUUGUUUUGUCAGUUUUUGCUUCUGUCUUGCCUGGAGGCCUGACACCUCCUGUCUUCCAGGUAAAUUGACUUCCCUUGUACAUCUUACCAGAAAGAUAUUUACCCUAACUUGUUACACAAACUAUUGCCACAGUACCUGUGGAUUUUUAAGUUAACUAACAUGUGUAUUUCUCUUUAAAGGUUUUGUGCACAGACCAAACAAAUCACCCUCAGUCUUCCCAGCAGUCAGAUGUGGUAACUAAGACUAGGACGGAUAAUAUAGGUUGUGAGGUGGCAAACAACUUAGGGUCCUAAGAUUUUGCCAAGACUGUCAUCAUUACCUGGAGUAUAAUGGGACUAACUAUACCUCCCUUUAAGGACAAUGGAAACAUUCUAUUGAAACCAUCCUCACAGGGUUAACAAGAAUUAGAUGCUGGGUUCUGGACAGAAAUAUAGUUGUAAUUAAGCAUUAAUCAGGCUGCACUUUGGCCCACUUCUUCGUAACCAAAAGUCCCAGAGCACCAGAUGCUAACCAUUUGCCUCCUCAUUGUUCCUACAGAGAAGAUUUCUGAUGUUAGAAUCAUAAGGCCUUUGUUUGUUUAAAAAUGGCUUAAGAUGUUUUUCAGAUCCUGAAUUCCAGCAAAAGAGCUAUUGCCAACCAGUUUGAAGACCGCCCCCCGCCUCUCCCCAAGAGGAACUGAAUCAGCAUGAAAAUGCAGUUUCUUCAUCUCACCAUCCUGUAUUCUUCAACCAGUGAUCCCCCACCUCGGUCACUCCAACUCCCUUAAAAUACCUAGACCUAAACGGCUCAGACAGGCAGAUUUGAGGUUUCCCCCUGUCUCCUUAUUCGGCAGCCUUAUGAUUAAACUUCCUUCUCUGCUGCAACCCUGUGUCUCGGUGUAUUGACUUGCCAUGAAUUAGGCAACAAACCUAUUACAGUUACAGUUACUUUUUUAAAGGAAAUUCAAUCGUUGGAUUGGUCCACCUGCUUAUUUCUUCCCUUUUCAAAAAAAAUGUCUACAUAUUGAAUUUUUAUACAUUAAGUGGUUCAUGAAACCCCUGAAAUGUGUUAGUAAAUAGGGCAAUUAUGAAAUAUUUGGACAUAGCUAGACUUUAAAAAUUGUUAAUCUGAAGGUCAGAUAGACUUGGCCUUCUCCAGCUUUCGUGAUUAUUCCCUCAGCAGCAAGCUAGUCUUAGGCAGAGCAAGUUUAAAGACAUUCAUGGUGCUCACUCUGCAAAACUGCACAAUUCUCAACAUGCACAGAGGCAGACAUGAUAGGGCUCAGCCCUGGAAUUGAUAACACUAGCCAACACACUUGCUAAGAAUUUAUAAGAUGUAGACCCUGUUAUUAUCCUGUCUUGCAAGUGAUGAGAAAACUAAGGCUUAAGGAUGUUAAGUAUUAUUAGUUCAAGGCCAACGGUAAGUGGCAAAGCUCAGAUUUGAAUCCAGGCAGUCCCACCCUAAAGGCCAUUCUCUUAGUCUGUGUACUGCCCUCCUUGCUAAAAGAGCUCACCUCUCUAGCCACUUCCUUCUCCCUGUCCCAUCUCCCCUUGUACCCUCCAAAUAGUCUUCUUAGCCUCUUCACCUUAUCUACUGGCCUAUUUCUGCCUUGAGGACCUCCCACCUCCUCGCCUGCUGGACUUCUUCCUUACCUGCCUUGUUAAUACAACCCUGCCCAGCACCUGCCUCCCUGGUCACACUACAGCCAGGUAGCAGAAACCAAAAUGGGCCUGGAUUUCCCCAACCAACUUGGUUCUACUUGCAAGAUUCUCAGAUCAUGCUGAAUCCUGCCUAGGCUACCCUCCCACUUUCUUUUCUUUACCAUCUGACCACAUGCCUAAAUAAACAUCACUUGGGCGAAUACAGUGUUCCCCAAAUUGCAUUCAUUCCCAUUUUGUCAUGAUUUUUCUUAUCUUUGUGGACCACCUAGAGCAUUAUUUACUUGAUUCACUUUUUGAAUUUUAGUAUAUAUAUCUUAAACUUUAUAUUUCAGCCUCAAAGAAAAACAAGUACUACCUGUAAUUAGAAGUUAAGCAUAAAAAUAAACAUAAGAGAAAAACAAUGCUGAUGAUUUCCAGCUCUGCAUAGUUGCUUGCCUUAGCAACUAGGAGUGAGAUUCAGUCUCUGUGUUAAAAAGUGAGGCUAGCCACCAUUAGAGGGGCAUUUAAUUCUAGCACCAAACCGAAACUCUCCAUUUGGCAUAUUCAGAAGGAUUAAAGAGAAUAACCUACUGAGAGAUUCAAUGUAGAUCACUUAAGAUUAUCUUAAACAGGAAUAUGACUGACUCCCAACUUUGGAGAAACAGCAGUGGAGGCCAGAUCUUAAACCCAGAGCAAGCUGGCUUUAGACUUGCUUCAACCCUAAACCAGUACUCCUUUCCACCCACCCACCUCCCCCCAACCCCUGCAGGCAUAUCAAGAAGACAAGGUGCAUGGGGGAAAACCAAAGAGUCAGCUUCCCUAGGGCUGAUGGGUCAAAUCUCAGUGCUUGCCUCUGACAUUUUGCUUGCCGACAGUCUGUCUUGAAAACCAACAGGUUGCAAAGAAGAAUGUGAACACCUAUAUCCAGAGAUGCCCUAUAUAAGAAUAAAGACUAUAAGACCAAAAAGAUGUUCUUGACUUAAUGUUUGGGGUGGACAUACCUAGUUAUACGAUUUGGCUGUUUCCCCACCCACAUCUCAUCUUGAAUUGUAGCUCCCAUAAUCCCCACAUGUCAUGGGAGGGACCCAGUGGGAGGUAACUGAAUCAAGGGGGAGGGUCUUUCCCAUGCUGUUCUCAUGAUUGAUAGUGAUGGUUUUAUAAAGGACAUUUCCCCUGAAUACGCUGUCUUGCCUGCUGCCAUGUAAGAUGUGGCUUUGCUCCUCUUUUGCCUUCCUCCAUGAUUGCGAGUCCAUUAAACCUCAUUCCUUUAUAAAUUA